CUUGGGAGUAAACGCUAAUUAAUUCAACAGCAGCUUUUAAGCCUUCUGUGCAAGUUUAGGAAGAGGCCACUCAACCUAGCUAGAUCCUAGGAGCCUUAAACGUCCAGAAUGCAAACCCUUCCCUAGAAGGAAUUCCCCUCAACCCUCACCCCACUUCACCUUUUGAUGGUUUACUCAAGGGCCUCAAAAUGCUACAGCUGCAGAGGCUGAAGGUUCUGAACAUGAGACUCACCUGGGAGACCCGGGCCUCGCCCCUCAGCCUCCCUGACCAACUCAAUCAGCCUCUUGCCCGGGGCGGGCUCAAAACUCCCCAAGUGAUUCCAAUCUGCGUUCACGCAUAAGAACCAUCGGCGUGGGGGUAGAAUCAGCCCUGUGAGGUGGGGCCAAGGGCUGCGAAACACCUGCCAUCAGCUGAGGGCAUUUAAGGCUGACCAAGGGGCUGGAGGCUGCGGCUCCUGGCCAGGUAACUUACUACUUCCAGUCAAUAUGCCGACCUUAGAUGCUCCAGAAGAGAGGCGGAGAAAAUUUAAGUACCGAGGCAAAGAUGUGUCUCUGAGGCGACAGCAGAGGAUGGCGGUCAGUCUGGAGCUCCGAAAGGCCAAGAAAGAUGAACAGACCUUAAAGAGAAGGAAUAUCACGAGCUUCUGCCCUGACACACCUUCUGAAAAAACAGCCAAAGGGGUGGCGGUCAGCCUCACUCUGGGUGAAAUAAUCAAAGGUGUGAAUAGCUCAGAUCCAGUCCUAUGUUUCCAGGCCACCCAGACAGCCAGGAAAAUGCUAUCCCAGGAAAAGAACCCCCCUCUGAAACUGGUCAUUGAAGCGGGCCUCAUUCCCAGGAUGGUGGAGUUCCUGAAGUCAUCACUUUACCCCUGCUUGCAGUUUGAGGCUGCCUGGGCCCUGACCAACAUCGCUUCAGGGACUUCGGAGCAGACUCGUGCCGUGGUAGAAGGGGGAGCCAUCCAGCCCUUGAUUGAGCUCCUGUCUUCCUCCAACGUGGCUGUGUGUGAACAGGCAGUGUGGGCUCUUGGUAAUAUAGCCGGUGAUGGCCCAGAGUUCAGAGAUAACGUCAUCACAAGCAAUGCCAUCCCACAUCUCCUAGCCUUGAUUUCACCCACCCUGCCGAUCACAUUUCUGCGGAACAUCACGUGGACCUUGUCGAAUCUGUGCCGAAACAAGAACCCAUACCCUUGCGACACUGCGGUGAAGCAGAUACUGCCGGCCCUCCUUCACCUCCUGCAGCACCAGGACAGUGAGGUUCUCUCGGAUGCCUGCUGGGCACUGUCCUACCUCACCGACGGCUCCAACAAGCGCAUCGGCCAAGUGGUUAACACGGGGGUCCUGCCCAGGCUGGUAGUGCUCAUGACCAGCUCAGAACUCAAUGUCUUGACUCCUUCUCUCCGCACCGUGGGGAACAUUGUCACGGGCACAGAUGAGCAGACGCAGAUGGCCAUUGAUGCGGGUAUGCUGAACGUGCUCCCCCAGCUCCUGCAACACAACAAGCCCUCCAUCCAGAAGGAGGCAGCCUGGGCCCUGAGCAACGUAGCAGCGGGGCCUUGUCACCACAUCCAGCAGCUGCUUGCCUACGACGUCUUGCCUCCCUUGGUGGCUCUGCUAAAAAACGGAGAAUUUAAAGUCCAGAAAGAGGCUGUCUGGAUGGUGGCGAACUUUGCAACAGGGGCCACCAUGGAUCAGCUGAUCCAGCUCGUCCACUCUGGGGUCCUGGAGCCACUGGUGAAUCUGCUCACUGCCCCAGAUGUUAAAAUUGUUCUCAUCAUCCUUGAUGUCAUCUCUUGCAUCCUCCAGGCGGCAGAGAAACGGUCUGAGAAGGAAAACCUGUGUCUUCUGAUAGAAGAACUUGGUGGGAUCGAUAGAAUUGAGGCUUUACAGCUGCAUGAGAACCGUCAAAUUGGCCAGUCGGCUUUGAACAUCAUCGAGAAGCACUUUGGUGAGGUAAGUGACUUAGGAGCGUGGAGGAGUAUCCAGGGGUCUUGGUGGGGCAGCUCUGCAGAGGGUCACCCUGCCGGGGCCUGGGCUGUUGCGUGUGGCAGGUGACUGGGCAGGUGGUCUUCACUCCUGCCACAUCCUCUGAAGUUAAUGUGUCUCGCCUAUCCCUGCUGUAUCGGGUCAUCUUUGAGUAGUGACAUCUUGGUGCCUGGAAGCUAUUCUAAUUCCUUGGGAGCUUGUCUGGCUGCCUCUGGCUUAAAACUUCACUUUACUGGUCUCCUUUUUGGGAGAGGUAUGGCAGGGGAGAGGAUUUGAUGCUGAAGUGACUUUUUUUUUUUUUUUUUUUUUUUUUUGAGAUGGUUUCACUCUGUUGCCCAGGCUGGAGGACAGAGGCGCCAUCUCAGCUCACUGCAACUUCUGCCUUCCAGAUUCAGUUGAUUCUUGAGCCUCAUUGACCCGAGAAGCUGGGAUUAGAGAGAUGUACUACGACGCCCAGCUAAUCUUUAGUAGAGACAGGGUUUCCCUGUGUUAGCCAGGCUGGUCUCAAACUCCUGGCCUCAAGUGAUCCACCCGCCUUGGCGUAAUCCCAAAGUGCUGGGAUCACAGGCGUGAGCCACCACACCCGGCCCGUCUCCACAACAGUUUUUAUCUUCCCAAACUGAAACUCCCUACCCGUUAACUACAAAGUCCCCAACACACCUUUCCCCUAGCCCUUUUAGUAACCAUCAUUUUGCUUUCUGUCUCUAUGAAUUUGACUAUUCUAGGGACCUCAUGAGUGGAAUUGUACAGUAUUUGUCCUUUUGUGACUGAUAUAUUUCCUCUUGGCAUACCAUCUUCAAGAUUCAUCCGUGUUGUAGCAUGUCAGGAUUGCUUUCCUUUUUAAGGCUAACACUCCAUUGAAUGUAUAUGCUGCAUUAUAUAUAUUCAUUUACCUGUCAAUCGACAUGUGAGUUUCUUCUACCAUUUUGCUAUGGUGAAUACACUGCUAUGAACAUGGGUGUGUAAGCCUGUUAGAGUCCCUGCUUCCAAUUUUUUUUUGUUUGUAAAGACAGGGUCCUGCUCUGUCACCCAGGCUGGAAGGCAA